GAGUCGCUGACCGAGCGCACCCCGCCCCCGGCGCCAUCUUCCCGACCGCGAGCCGUCCAGGUCUCAGUGCUGUGCCCCCCCCAGAGCCUAGAGGAUGUUUCAUGGGAUCCCAGCCACGCCGGGCAUAGGAGCCCCUGGGAACAAGCCGGAGCUGUAUGAGGAAGUGAAGUUGUACAAGAACGCCCGGGAGAGGGAGAAGUACGACAACAUGGCAGAGCUGUUUGCGGUGGUGAAGACAAUGCAAGCCCUGGAGAAGGCCUACAUCAAGGACUGUGUCUCCCCCAGCGAGUACACUGCAGCCUGCUCCCGGCUCCUGGUCCAAUACAAAGCUGCCUUCAGGCAGGUCCAGGGCUCAGAAAUCAGCUCUAUUGACGAAUUCUGCCGCAAGUUCCGCCUGGACUGCCCGCUGGCCAUGGAGCGGAUCAAGGAGGACCGGCCCAUCACCAUCAAGGACGACAAGGGCAACCUCAACCGCUGCAUCGCAGACGUGGUCUCGCUCUUCAUCACGGUCAUGGACAAGCUGCGUCUGGAGAUCCGCGCCAUGGAUGAGAUCCAGCCCGACCUGCGAGAGCUGAUGGAGACCAUGCACCGCAUGAGCCACCUCCCACCCGACUUUGAGGGCCGCCAGACGGUCAGCCAGUGGUGGGUGUCCCUCCCAGCCAGGCAGAGCCCCGCAGUGCCCGAGACCCUCCCAGCCAGGCGGAGCCCCGCAGUGCCCCUGAGGCCCUCAGCCCCCACAUGCCCUGUGCUGCACUCCCAGGCUGCAGACCCUGAGCGGCAUGUCGGCGUCAGAUGAGCUGGACGACUCACAGGUGCGUCAGAUGCUGUUCGACCUGGAGUCAGCCUACAACGCCUUCAACCGCUUCCUGCAUGCCUGAGCCCGGGGCACUAGCCCUUGCACAGAAGGGCAGAGUCUGAGGCGAUGGCUCCUGGUCCCCUGUCCGCCACACAGGCCGUGGUCAUCCACACAACUCACUGUCUGCAGCUGCCUGUCUGGUGUCUGUCUUUGGUGUCAGAACUUUGGGGGCCGGGCCCCUCCCCACAAUAAAGAUGCUCUCCGACCUUC